CACACACCUGGGGGGAGACAGGAGCCUGGGGCCGGUGGGCCCACACAUCACCAGCUGCUCCGUUCUACCAUUUCUUCAGCCCUCUUGGCUGUGCCUGCAGCUCUGCCCCUCCCCUCUCUGCACCUACCACCCAGAGAGGGCUUGUUGAGCUCAGAGAUCCCACCUAGGCCAAUCCACUGGGUUCUGCGGCAGCGAUGGCCUGCCUGAUCUUCCACCUGCUCUCCCAGGGCCAAAGCCAGACCUGCUGAGCCCCUCCCUCCAGCCGGCUGGUCUGAGCAGUCACAGCCCGGCUUUGGGCUCCGAUGGCAGCAGACGGCAGGUAGGGGUCCAGCUGCUGGAGCGAGGGCCGGCCACCUAUCACAGCCAAGGAGAUGAGCACAAGCACUACUUACUGGCCUAGGUUGUCAGAGAAGUUGAUGCUCUCACUCAUCUUUCCUCCAAUCUUUCCCCUAUGCCUGGUUCAUGGCUGAAAUCGUGUUUGACCAGCUGUGUGUGUCUCUCAAUCCAGUCAAGUAGACGUCUACAAUUAACCAUCAGAAUAUUUAUGCCUGAUUCAUGGCUGAAAUCGUGUUUGACCAGCUAUGUGUGUCUCUCAAUCCAGUCAAGUAGACGUCUACAAUUAACCAUCAGAAUAUUUAUGCCUGAUUCAUGGCUGAAAUCGUGUUUGACCAGCUAUGUGUGUCUUUCAAUCCAGUCAAGUAGAUGUCUACAAUUAACCAUCAGAAUAUUUAUGCCUGAUUCAUGGCUGAAAUCGUGUUUGACCAGCUAUGUGUGUCUUUCAAUCCAGUCAAGUAGAUGUCUACAAUUAACCAUCAGAAUAUUUAUGCCUGAUUCAUGGCUGAAAUCGUGUUUGACCAGCUAUGUGUGUCUCUCAAUCCAAUCAAGUAGAUGCCUAAAGUUAACCGUCAGAAUAUUUAUGCCUGAUUCAUGGCUGAAAUCGUGUUUGACCAGCUAUGUGUGUCUCUCAAUCCAGUCAAGUAGAUGUCUAAAGUUAACCAUCAGAAUAUUUAUGCCUGAUUCAUGGCUGAAAUCGUGUUUGACCAGCUAUGUGUGUCUCUCAAUCCAAUCAAGUAGAUGCCUAAAGUUAACCGUCAGAAUAUUUAUGCCUGAUUCAUGGCUGAAAUCGUGUUUGACCAGCUAUGUGUGUCUCUCAAUCCAGUCAAGUAGAUGUCUAAAAUUAACCGUCAGAAUAUUUAUGCCUGAUUCAUGGCUGAAAUUGUGUUUGACCAGCUAUGUGUGUCUCUCAAUCCACUCAAGUAGAUGUCUAAAAUUAACCAUCAGAAUAUUUAUGCCUGAUUCAUGGCUGAAAUCGUGUUUGACCAGCUAUGUGUGUCUCUCAAUCCGAUCAAGUAGAUGUCUAAAAUUAACCGUCAAAAUAUUUAUGCCUGAUUCAUGGCUGAAAUUGUGUUUGACCAGCUAUGUGUGUCUCUUAAUCCACUCAAGUAGAUGUCUAAAAUUAACCAUCAGAAUAUUUAUGGCUGAUUCAUGGCUGAAAUCAUGUUUGACCAGCUAUGUGUGUCUCUUAAUCCAGUCAAGUAGAUGUCUAAAAUUAACCAUCAGAAUAUUUAUGCCUGAUUCAUGGCUGAAAUCGUGUUUGACCACUAUGUGUGUCUCUCAAUCCGAUCAAGUAGAUGUCUGA